AGAGCGCUUGGAGCCAGCGCUGCAGGGAGAUAGCAGCGCGCAGCCCGCAGAGGCGCUGCGGCCCGUGCAGCCCCGGAGGCCCCUCGCGGAGAAGGCGGCGGCGGAGGAGAGGCCGAGUUACCGCCCGCCGCCCGCGCCCCCCCAACCCCGCCGCCGCCGCCGCCGCCGCCACUGCCCCCCCUCCCCGCGGCGCCGCAUCUUGAAUGGAAACAUGGCGGUGCCGGCUCGGACCUGCGGCGCCUCUCGGCCCGGCCCAGCGCGGACUGCGCGCCCCUGGCCCGGCUGCGGCCCCCACCCUGGCCCCGGCACCCGGCGCCCGACGUCCGGGCCCCCGCGCCCGCUGUGGCUGCUGCUGCCGCUUCUACCGCUGCUCGCCGCCCCCGGCGCCUCUGCCUACAGCUUCCCCCAGCAGCACACGAUGCAGCACUGGGCCCGGCGUCUGGAGCAGGAGGUCGACGGCGUGAUGCGGAUUUUUGGAGGCGUCCAGCAGCUCCGUGAGAUUUACAAGGACAACCGGAACCUGUUCGAGGUACAGGAGAAUGAGCCUCAGAAGUUGGUGGAGAAGGUGGCAGGGGACAUUGAGAGCCUUCUGGACAGGAAGGUGCAGGCCCUGAAGAGACUGGCUGAUGCUGCAGAGAACUUCCAGAAAGCACACCGCUGGCAGGACAACAUCAAGGAGGAAGACAUCGUGUACUAUGACGCCAAGGCUGACGCUGAGCUGGACGACCCUGAGAGUGAGGAUGUGGAAAGGGGGUCUAAGGCCAGCACCCUAAGGCUGGACUUCAUCGAGGACCCAAACUUCAAGAACAAGGUCAACUAUUCAUACGCGGCUGUACAGAUCCCUACGGACAUCUACAAAGGCUCCACUGUCAUCCUCAAUGAGCUCAACUGGACAGAGGCCCUGGAGAAUGUGUUCAUGGAAAACCGCAGACAAGACCCCACACUGCUGUGGCAGGUCUUCGGCAGCGCCACAGGAGUCACUCGCUACUACCCGGCCACCCCGUGGCGAGCCCCCAAGAAGAUCGACCUGUACGAUGUCCGAAGGAGACCCUGGUAUAUCCAGGGGGCCUCGUCACCCAAAGACAUGGUCAUCAUCGUGGAUGUGAGUGGCAGUGUGAGCGGCCUGACCCUGAAGCUGAUGAAGACAUCUGUCUGCGAGAUGCUGGACACGCUGUCUGAUGAUGACUAUGUGAAUGUGGCCUCGUUCAACGAGAAGGCACAGCCUGUGUCAUGCUUCACACACCUGGUGCAGGCCAAUGUGCGCAACAAGAAGGUGUUCAAGGAAGCUGUGCAGGGCAUGGUGGCCAAGGGCACCACAGGCUACAAGGCCGGCUUUGAGUAUGCCUUUGACCAGCUGCAGAACUCCAACAUCACUCGGGCCAACUGCAACAAGAUGAUCAUGAUGUUCACGGAUGGUGGUGAGGACCGCGUGCAGGACGUCUUUGAGAAGUACAAUUGGCCAAACCGGACGGUGCGCGUGUUUACUUUCUCCGUGGGGCAGCAUAACUAUGACGUCACACCGCUGCAGUGGAUGGCCUGUGCCAACAAAGGCUACUAUUUUGAGAUCCCUUCCAUCGGAGCCAUCCGCAUCAACACACAGGAAUAUCUAGAUGUGUUGGGCAGGCCCAUGGUGCUGGCAGGCAAGGAGGCCAAGCAGGUGCAGUGGACCAACGUGUAUGAGGAUGCACUGGGACUGGGGUUGGUGGUAACAGGGACCCUCCCUGUUUUCAACCUGACACAGGAUGGCCCUGGGGAAAAGAAGAACCAGCUGAUCCUGGGCGUGAUGGGCAUUGACGUGGCUCUGAAUGACAUCAAGAGGCUGACCCCCAACUACACGCUUGGAGCCAACGGCUAUGUGUUUGCCAUUGACCUGAACGGCUACGUGUUGCUGCACCCCAAUCUCAAGCCCCAGACCACCAACUUCCGGGAGCCUGUGACUCUGGACUUCCUGGAUGCGGAGCUAGAGGAUGAGAACAAGGAAGAGAUCCGUCGGAGCAUGAUUGAUGGCAACAAGGGCCACAAGCAGAUCAGAACGUUGGUCAAGUCCCUGGAUGAGAGGUACAUAGAUGAGGUGACACGGAACUACACCUGGGUGCCUAUAAGGAGCACUAACUACAGCCUGGGGCUGGUGCUCCCACCCUACAGCACCUUCUACCUCCAAGCCAAUCUCAGUGACCAGAUCCUGCAGGUCAAGUUGCCAAUCAGCAAACUGAAGGAUUUUGAGUUCCUGCUCCCCAGCAGCUUUGAGUCUGAAGGACACGUUUUCAUUGCUCCCAGAGAGUACUGCAAGGACCUGAAUGCCUCAGACAACAACACCGAGUUCCUGAAAAACUUUAUUGAGCUCAUGGAGAAAGUGACUCCAGACUCCAAGCAGUGCAACAACUUCCUUCUGCACAACCUGAUCUUGGACACGGGCAUCACGCAGCAGCUGGUAGAGCGUGUGUGGAGGGACCAGGAUCUCAACACGUACAGCCUACUGGCCGUGUUCGCUGCCACAGACGGUGGCAUCACCCGAGUCUUCCCCAACAAGGCAGCUGAGGACUGGACAGAGAACCCUGAGCCCUUCAAUGCCAGCUUCUACCGCCGCAGCCUGGAUAACCACGGUUAUGUCUUCAAGCCCCCACACCAGGAUGCCCUGUUAAGGCCGCUGGAGCUGGAGAAUGACACUGUGGGCAUCCUCGUCAGCACAGCUGUGGAGCUCAGCCUAGGCAGGCGCACACUGAGGCCAGCAGUGGUGGGCGUCAAGCUGGACCUAGAGGCUUGGGCUGAGAAGUUCAAGGUGCUAGCCAGCAACCGUACCCACCAAGACCAGCCUCAGAAGCAGUGCGGCCCCAACAGCCACUGUGAGAUGGACUGCGAGGUUAACAAUGAGGACUUACUCUGUGUCCUCAUUGAUGAUGGAGGAUUCCUGGUGCUGUCAAACCAGAACCAUCAGUGGGACCAGGUGGGCAGGUUCUUCAGUGAGGUGGAUGCCAACCUGAUGCUGGCACUCUACAAUAACUCCUUCUACACCCGCAAGGAGUCCUAUGACUAUCAGGCAGCCUGUGCCCCUCAGCCCCCUGGCAACCUGGGUGCUGCACCCCGGGGUGUCUUUGUGCCCACCGUUGCAGAUUUCCUUAACCUGGCCUGGUGGACCUCUGCUGCCGCCUGGUCCCUGUUCCAGCAGCUUCUCUACGGCCUCAUCUACCACAGCUGGUUCCAAGCAGACCCCGCGGAGGCCGAGGGGAGCCCCGAGACGCGCGAGAGCAGCUGCGUCAUGAAACAGACCCAGUACUACUUCGGCUCGGUAAACGCCUCCUACAACGCCAUCAUCGACUGCGGAAACUGCUCCAGGCUGUUCCACGCGCAGAGACUGACCAACACCAAUCUUCUCUUUGUGGUGGCCGAGAAGCCGCUGUGCAGCCAGUGCGAGGCUGGCCGGCUGCUGCAGAAGGAGACGCACUCGGACGGCCCGGAGCAGUGUGAGCUAGUGCAGAGACCGCGAUACCGGAGAGGCCCGCACAUCUGCUUCGACUACAACGCGACAGAAGAUACCUCAGACUGUGGCCGCGGGGCCUCCUUCCCGCCGUCGCUGGGCGUCCUGGUCUCCCUGCAACUGCUGCUCCUCCUGGGCCUGCCGCCCCGGCCGCAGCCUCAAGUCCUCGUCCACGCCUCUCGCCGCCUCUGAGCACCCUGCCCCACCCCACCUCCACUCCCACCUCACCCGGCCUCUUCGCCUUUCCCACCCUCCUGCCCCACACUCCCCGCCUUAGAGCCUCGUCCCUCCCUCACUGAAGGACCUGAGCUGGCCAGGCCCUGAGAGUCUGGUCUGCGCCUUGGGAUGGGGAGUCCCAAAGCGGGACGCCGCAGGUGUUUGGCACCCAAAUCACAUCUCACCUCCGAACUGUUCAAGUGUCCCCAGACCCUUCUUGCCUGCUGGGCUCCCCCCAGUGGGAUGGGACAGGGAGGCCACACGCACUGGUGCCAAAACCAGGCCUCUGCUGCCGCCCUUCCUGGAGGCUGCCUAUGUUGGGGGGGACCCUGCCUCAGCUGACCCGGCCUCUCUGCCCCACCCAAGCCCAAACUUGGUUUCUGUGAGAAUAGUGGAGGAAGGUGAGAUGGCCAGUUUGAAGCCUGUGCCUCCCAGCUUAAAUCCUAGCAGGAGAGAGGCUCUGGGGCAGCCCCCAUGGGCUCCUGCCCCUUUCAGGCCUACAGCCACAUCCCCAAGCCCACCAGGUGUCAGGAUAGUCACAGUGAUACCAGUUCAGACACUACCCCAUAUACACCUGGAACAUUGAGGAUGGAAACUGGACUCACAUUCGACAUACCCCACUGGGCACACGCACAAACACACACACUAUGGGGUGGGGUGGGUGUAGGGGCUUACAAAGCCUUACACAGGGCGAGGGGUUGGUGGGAGGGUUGGCACCUGCACACUCCAUCUCCUGCUCACCACCUGCCUCUAAUCUGAGCUGCAGCCUGGCUGGUCCUCCCAUUUCUAAAGCUGAAUGUCAAACAGUGCCAAAUGCUGGGGCAGGGGGUGAAGAACCCUCUGUCCCACCCCUAGCCACCAGUGUCCUCCAAGUGCCCCCUCACCUCUCCAGGUGCUCAUUGUAACCAUUUCUCACUAGUGUCAGGCCCCCAGUGGGACCACAUGCCACUGCCUGCACCUUUCGGCAGAGGAACCCCCACCAGACAUCACCCUUUGCCUUAGCAGGGGUGACUUUGUCUCUCCUGGCUGGGCCAUCCUUCCGCCAAUCUGGCCCUUACACACUCAGGCCUGUGCCCACUCCCUAUCUCCUUCCCACCCCUACACACACACUCCCUGCUUGCAGGAGGCCAAACUGUCCCUCCCUUGCUGAACACACACACACACACACACACACAGGUGGGGACUGGGCACAGCUCUUCACACCAUUCAUUCUGGUCAUUUCCCCCAAAGGCAUCCCAGCCUGGGGGCCAGUGGGGAACUGAGGGCAAGGGGAUAUAGUGAUGGGGCUCAGAUGGACUGGGAGGAGGGGGAGGGUGAUGCAUUAAUUAAUGGCUUCGUUAAUUAAUGUCAUGUUGCUUGUCGCUUUCUCAGUGUGUGUGUGUGGUCCAUGCCCACUGCUGGUGCCAGGGUGGGUGUCCAUGUGCACCCGGCCUGGAUGCCAGCUGUGUCCUUCGGGGGCGUGCGUGUAACUGUAGUGUAGUCAGGUGCUCAAUGGAGAAUAUAAACAUAUACAGAAAAAUAUAUAUUUUAAGUUUAAAAAACAGAAAAACAGACAAAACAAUCCCCAUCAGGUAGCUGUCUAACCCCCAGCUGGGUCUAAUCCUUCUCAUUACCCACCCGACCUGGCUGCCCCUCACCUUGGGCUGGGGGACUGGGGGGCCAUUUCCUUUUCUCUGCCCUUUUUUUGUUGUUCUAUUUUGUACAGACAAGUUGGAAAAACAACAGCGACAAAAAAGUCAAGAAACUUUGUAAAAUAUCGUGUGUGUGAUUCCUUGUAAAAUAUUUUCAAAUGGUUUAUUACAGAAGAUCAGUUAUUAAAUAAUGUUCAUAUUUUCACUUCAAAUGGUUCCCAUCCACUGUAUCAGCUUGGGGGUGAGGACUGGGUAGCUAUGAAGACAGUUGGCCAAGACCUCAGAGUCCCACUUAGUGCUCUGCAGGGGGUGAAGACCAUGGUAGCCCAGGUCCCUGUCAACCACAGGGCAUGGCACUUGCUUCCACCAGUUAUAAUAGGUGCCAGGCCCUUGACAUA